GCUUAUCCUGUGGAGGAGGUGGCUUCCAGCAGGGUGCUGGCAGGCGGAAACCCACCCCCAUGCCAGUGCCUUCAGCGGUGGCCUGCUGACCUCCCAGGGUGGGGGCCACCGCUUGGCACACAGUGGGAGCUCUGAGAACAUGGGCUAAAACAGAACUUGGGGAACUGGCUUUUCUUGGCCAGAGCAGCCUAUCCCCCGGGCCCCCUGGAGUCAGCCAGAUCCCUGGUUCCAGCCCCUCUCCCAGCUGCCUCUGGUGAGCCAACGGGGCCCAGUCCCCUCCUCCAGGGAACCCUGCACCCUGGGCACCCCACAGGGCUAUGUCUUCUCUGAGACUGUUCUGACACUUAGAAAACAGAUAACAGCCCCUCCAUGUGGGCUAUAUGAGGAGAGAGGAGCAGCAGGCAGGCAGCUCAGCCCAGCCUGGGCACAGCCAGUGCCCAUGGAUUCUGGCUGUAUCGGGAGCGCUGUCUUGCUCAUGGCUGCAUCCCACACCCUUGGCCCUGUGCCUGGCACACAGCAGGCACUUGACAGUAGGAAGCCAUCCCAUGCCCGGGGUGGCCCCAGGCUGUCAGGUUGGGAGCGGGCUGAGCCUUUGUCUGGGUCCUGGCUUCUGCUGCUCAGAACACCACUGGCUUUCUCUUCUCUCCCAAUUCUCUCACCCUCUCAGCCUGGCUUGAGGACACGCCUCUUCCCCCCCUUCAGGAUCACCUUGCCAGACACAAUAUAUGUGUUUAAGAAGCAGACACAUUUGUUGAAUAAAAGAAUGAAGCAAUGGAUGAGGCGUGGGGGCAACCAAGCUGGCUGGCACAGGCAUCAAUACAUGUGGUGGCUCCUGGAGGGAGGCAGGGCAAGGGCAGCUGCAGGGCACUCACCCGGGCCUUGUCCUCCAUCUUCCCAAGGGCUGUCAGGGCUCCUCCAGUGGGUGCCCAAGGGUCCCUCCUUACCCUGGGCCUCUGGCCACCUUGAUCCCCAGCCUACCUGCUGAUCGCCCUUGUACUCGCCGAAGUGGAAGACUCGGGCUUUGAGCUCCAGCUCAGCUGCUGUGUCCUCCUCCUUGGUGAUGGACAUCAUCAUUGUGGUGACCCACUGCUUCAGCUGGUUGACCUCCCUGUCCCUGGAAGAGGGGAAAACCGGCAGGGCAUCAGUCACUCAGCACAGCCCUGGGCACAUCGCUUCUCUGAGCCUGUCUGUACAGUGCUUUGCCCCUACCAGCUGUCCUGAGGGCUGAAGGAUCAUGGGUGCCAAGUCUCUGCAUGCCCAGGGGGUCAGAAAUGCUGGUAGAAUGUAGGGGAAAAUGUAAAAUAUUUAACAAUCAACAUUAAAGAAAAUAAACAGCUUCAUUGAGGCAUAAUUCACAGACAAUAAAAUUAGCAUAACCAUCAUAAAA